ACGGACUUGUCUGAGGAAAGACAGGAAAGCGCCAGCAUCUCCACCUUCCCCGGAAGCCUCCCUUUGCCAGGCAGAAAGGGUUUCCCAUGGGGCCGCCCCUGGCGCCGCGCCCGGCCCACGUACCCGGGGAGGCCGGGCCCCGGAGGACGAGGGAAAGCAGGCCGGGCGCCGUGAGCUUCGCGGACGUGGCCGUGUACUUCUCUCCCGAGGAGUGGGAAUGCCUGCGGCCAGCGCAGAGGGCCCUGUACCGGGACGUGAUGCGGGAGACCUUCGGCCACCUGGGCGCGCUGGGAUUUUCAGUUCCCAAACCCGCUUUUAUCUCGUGGGUGGAAGGAGAAGUGGAGGCGUGGAGCCCGGAGGCCCAGGAUCCCGACGGUGAGAGCUCUGCAGCUUUCAGCAGGGGCCAAGGACAGGAAGCAGGAUCCAGGGAUGGGAAUGAGGAGAAGGAAAGGCUGAAGAAGUGUCCAAAACAAAAAGAGGUGGCGCAUGAAGUGGCUGUCAAGGAGUGGUGGCCCAGCGUCGCCUGCCCAGAGUUCUGCAACCCUAGGCAGAGCCCCAUGAAUCCCUGGCUCAAGGACACUCUGACCCGAAGACUGCCCCACUCUUGCCCAGACUGUGGCCGCAACUUCAGCUACCCUUCCCUCCUGGCCAGCCACCAGCGGGUCCACUCCGGGGAGCGGCCCUUCUCCUGCGGCCAGUGUCAGGCGCGUUUCUCCCAGCGCAGGUACCUGCUCCAGCAUCAGUUCAUCCACACCGGCGAGAAGCCCUACCCCUGCCCCGACUGCGGGCGCCGCUUCCGCCAGAGGGGUUCCCUGGCUAUCCACAGGCGGGCUCACACCGGGGAGAAGCCUUACGCGUGCUCAGACUGCAAGAGUCGCUUCACUUACCCCUACCUGCUGGCCAUCCACCAGCGCAAGCACACGGGCGAGAAGCCCUACAGCUGCCCCGAUUGCAGCCUCCGUUUCGCCUACACCUCCCUGCUGGCCAUCCACAGGCGCAUACACACCGGCGAGAAGCCCUACCCCUGUCCUGACUGCGGCCGCCGCUUCACCUAUUCUUCCCUCCUCCUCAGUCACCGGCGCAUUCACUCCGACAGCCGGCCCUUCCCCUGCGUGGAGUGUGGGAAAGGCUUCAAGCGCAAGACCGCCCUGGAAGCCCAUCGGUGGAUCCACCGCUCCUGCAGCGAGAGGCGCGCGUGGCAGCAGGCCGUGGUGGGGCGUUCAGAGCCCAUCCCUGUUUUGGGAGGCAAGGAUCCCCCAGUUCACUUCCGGCACUUUCCAGAUAUAUUUCAAGAGUGUGGGUGAUGGCGUUCACACAAACUGGUCAGCGUUUCCCUGGAGAGGAAGAGGCAAGGUUUGUGUAUUUGGGGGAUAAGGAAAGGAAGUGGGCGUUUGAGGAAAACAAAGUUCUGCCUUAGGUAAAAAGCAGAGGUAGGGGCACAGAGGGCUGUGGGGAGGAGGCAGGAAUCUGAAAAGGUGCCUGGGGGUUGACCCCAUUUUCUGAAGCUCCAGCACACAGGGCCCCGUGUUCACGUCCCAUCCUUCACUGAAAACCAUUCACCUAACUGGCUUUUCCUUCAUGAUUGUUCUCUCCCUUGUAGCUCUCUGCUUUUUGGCCUGUAUCUCUCCUACUCCUCUGAGAUGGGGUCCCCUACAUUCCAGUGCCUAUUAAAGGAGCCUGCACCCACUCUGGACCCCCCAGAAUAGAGGGGAUACCUCAGGCCUGUCCCUCGGCUGGUGGGGGGGGCGGAGCUCAUCCCAGGAUUCUUUUCUUUUUUUUGAGAUGGAGUCAUGCUCUGUCGCCCAGGCUGGAGUGCAGUGGCGUGAUCUCGGCUCACUGCAACCUCUGCCUCCUGGGUUCAAGCCAUUCUCUGCCUCAGCCUUCCCAUUAGCUGGGAUUACAGGCAUGCGCCACCAGGCCCAGCUAAUUUUUGUGCUGUUAGUAGAGACGGGGUUCCACCAUCUUGGCCAGGCUGGUCUUGAAUUCCUGACCUCGUGAUCCACCCGCCUCGGCGUCUCAAAGUGCUGGGAUUACAAGCGUGAGCCACCGACCCCUGCCGAGGAUUCUGCCUUUUACCAAUGCAGGUGAAACAUCUGGCAAGGAGACACCUGGAGUGUAGGUGUUCCUUGGUCUUGAAGACCUAGAGGUGGCCAUAGAGAGGACAGUGGCCUCAGGUGGGGAACUCCCCCCCCACUCUCAUUCUGCAAGUGCACAAACUAUCAAACAUAGCGGACUCUGGAACUGGGCCAACUCUUCACUGUAUGCAUUAGUGAUUGCAGUGUUUUUUUCUUCUUCAGAUAUUUGCAUGUUCCCUGGAUUUUGUAUUUUUUGAUAAAGAUAUAUUCUUGGGCCACAGUAGCUGGAGAUAUAAUGCCGGAGGAUUCUUUUUUUUUUUUUUUUUUUUGAGACAGAGUCUGUCUCUAUUGCCUGGGCUGGAGUGCAGUGGCCCAAGCUACGCUCACUGCAAGCUCCACCUCCUGGGUUCACACCAUUCUCCUGCUUCAGUCUCCCGAGUAGCUGGAAUUACAAGCACCCGCCACCACGCCCAACUAAUAUUUUGUAUUUUUAGUAGAGACGGGGGUUUCACCGUGUUAGCCAGGAUGGUCUCGAUCUCCUGACUUCGUGAUCCUCCCGCCUCGGCCUCCCAAAGUGCUGGGAUUACAGGCGUGAGCCACUGCACCCAGCCUCUUUUUUUUUUUGAGAUGGAGUUUCGCUCUUGUUGCCCAGGCUAGAGUGCAAUGGCAUGAUCUUGGCUCACUGCAACCUCCGCCUCCUAGGUUCAAGCGAUUCUCCUGCCCCAGCCUCUUGAGUAGCUGGGAUUACAGGCACCCACGACCAUGCCUGGCUAAUUGCAUUUUUACUAGAGACAGGUUUCACCAUGUUGGCCAGGCUGGUCUCCAAUUCCUGACCUCAGGUGAUCCACCCGACUUGGCCUCCCAAAGUUCUGGGAUUACAUUUUUUUUUUAAAGAAAGAAUAAAUUAAUUGUGAUUAAAGUUGAAAUCAAGGCAUAGUCUUUCCAGUCUAAUUUUUACUGUAAUGCUUGUAUGUCAACAGUUAUGAAGGCCAGGCGCGGUGGCUCACGCCUGUAAUCCUAGCAGUUUGGGAGGCUGAGGAGGGUGGAUCACUUAAGGUCAAGAGUUCAAGACCAGCCUGGCCAAUAUGGUGAAACCCCAUCUCUACUAAAAAUACCAAAAAAAAAAAAAAAAA